AAGGAAGUCUUCCGCUCGCUCCGGAGCGAGGAGCCUGUAGAGAGGCUGUUCCCAGCUCCAGCUCUAACCUCGCCUACACCUUGGGCGGGCCCAAGUGUCACGUUUGCAAUUGCUCAGGAAGGAUCCGGCCCGUCUCCGGAGGCAAGUCGGGCUGCGGUUUUUGCUGCUUAUCUGGGAAGGCGAUGCCUAAGGGACAUGCUGCUUGCUAGGCAGCACCCUGCCGGGAUCCGACUGCGAUAGUUAGCUCUCCCUGGCCCUGAAGCCAUCGCCGGGGCGCCUGUUCUCUGUCCGGACCAGCCAGCGCUCCUCAGGAGUCUCACUGAAACAGAACCAUGGGUCAUCCCCCGCUGGAGUUCAGCGACUGCUACCUGGACAGCCCCGAUUUCCGCGAGAGGCUCAAGUGUUAUGAGCAGGAACUGGAGAGGACCAACAAAUUCAUCAAAGACGUAAUCAAAGACGGCAACGCGCUUAUCAGCGCUAUGAGAAAUUAUUCUUCUGCUGUUCAGAAAUUUUCCCAGACGCUGCAGUCAUUUCAGUUUGAUUUCAUUGGAGACACUCUGACUGAUGAUGAAAUUAACAUCGCUGAAUCCUUCAAGGAAUUUGCUGAAUUGCUCAACGAGGUAGAAAAUGAGAGGAUGAUGAUGGUACACAAUGCUAGUGAUUUGCUGAUUAAACCCUUGGAAAAUUUCCGGAAGGAACAAAUAGGCUUCACCAAGGAGCGGAAAAAGAAAUUUGAAAAGGAUGGUGAGAGGUUUUAUUCUUUACUGGAUCGGCACUUACACCUGUCUUCAAAAAAGAAAGAAUCUCAGUUACAAGAGGCAGACCUACAGGUGGACAAGGAGAGGCACAAUUUUUUCGAGUCCUCUCUUGAUUAUGUUUAUCAAAUCCAGGAAGUUCAGGAGUCCAAGAAGUUCAAUAUUGUGGAGCCUGUCUUGGCCUUUCUUCAUAGUCUGUUCAUUUCUAACAGCCUGACUGUGGAGCUCACACAGGAUUUCCUCCCAUACAAACAACAGCUCCAACUCAGUUUACAGAAUACAAGAAAUCAUUUCUCCAGUACCCGGGAAGAGAUGGAAGAACUUAAGAAAAGGAUGAAAGAAGCUCCCCAGACAUGCAAACUUCCAGGACAGCCAACUAUUGAAGGCUAUCUCUAUACACAAGAGAAAUGGGCUUUAGGAAUAUCCUGGGUGAAAUACUAUUGCCAGUAUGAGAAAGAGACCAAAACACUGACCAUGACGCCUAUGGAGCAGAAGCCAGGUGCUAAGCAGGGGCCCUUGGACUUAACACUGAAGUACUGUGUGAGAAGGAAGACGGAGUCUAUCGACAAGAGGUUCUGUUUUGACAUAGAAACUAAUGAAAGGCCAGGAACCAUCACUCUGCAGGCCCUUUCAGAAGCUAACAGAAGGCUAUGGAUGGAAGCCAUGGAUGGGAAAGAACCUAUCUACCACAGCCCUAUAACAAAACAGCAAGAAAUGGAGCUAAAUGAAGUGGGCUUCAAGUUUGUCAGGAAGUGCAUCAAUAUUAUUGAGACCAAAGGGAUCAAGACAGAAGGGUUGUACCGCACUGUGGGCAGCAAUAUUCAGGUUCAGAAGCUGCUGAAUGCCUUUUUUGAUCCUAAAUGCCCAGGAGAUGUUGAUUUUCAUAAUAGUGACUGGGACAUUAAGACAAUCACCAGCUCCUUGAAAUUCUACCUCAGGAAUCUUUCUGAACCUGUCAUGACCUAUAGACUUCACAAAGAGCUGGUCUCUGCUGCCAAGUCUGACAACCUGGAUUACCGCCUAGGAGCUAUUCACUCCCUGGUAUAUAAGCUACCAGAAAAGAACCGAGAGAUGCUGGAACUUCUGAUAAGACACUUGGUCAAUGUGUGUGAGCACAGCAAAGAGAAUCUUAUGACCCCCUCCAACAUGGGAGUAAUCUUUGGGCCCACCCUGAUGAGAGCUCAGGAGGACACUGUGGCCGCCAUGAUGAACAUCAAAUUCCAGAACAUAGUGGUGGAAAUACUAAUCGAGCACUUUGGCAAGAAAUUGCCAUAGCCACUCCAGCCUUCAGUAAGCACCAUCCUGAUCAAUCAGCAGUCAUCAACAUAGAAGCAAGACCCUCCACCAGCAAAAAAGGGUAUGAUUUGCCAAAGGCUCUGGUGAUUGUCAGCAUUUUUUAGCAAUAAAUUAUUUUUAAUGAAGGGAUGUAUACCUUAUUUUUAGGAAUCAUGCUAUUGCACACUUACUAGACUACAGUAUAGUAUAAGCACCAUGAAACCAGAAAAAAUUGUGUGGCUCAGUUUAUUGUGAUACAUAUUUUAUUCUGGUGGUCUGGAACCAAAUCCACACUAUCUCCUAGGUAUGUCUGUAUGUUACCUCAUUCAACCAUCACAACAACCCUAUGAGGUAGAUGGUAUCACUAUUCUCAUUUUGCAGCUGACAUUUUCAAAAUGCAAACUGAGCUUCAAGUUUGAGAUUCAUAUAGUUUAAGUUUCUUGCCCCUGGUUACAUAGCAAAGCUCCAACACAACUGACUCUGACUCUGUCCUGACUCUUUGACCUCUACUUUGUACUCUCUCACCUCUAUUUUGUACUCUCUCUUCCCAAUUAUAGUUGGUGAAGGAAUAAAUGAAAAAAAAAGUUCUAUUAUUUAAUAUGCUCUAAAGGGCCUGGUAGCCAAAAUUCAUCCAUUCAUUUUAAAAACUGUCAUUGAGCUGCUUUAUCUUGCCUCGUGCCCUACUCAGCCCUAGUCUCUAGAGAGGAAUCACGAAAAAAAAUCUCUGCUGUCAGAAAAGUUAUGGGACUUGGGGGUAUCUGGAACCAACUAACACUCAGGAUGCAGUGUAAUAAAGACUGUGGUGAAGAUGUGCAUUGGAUGCUGUGGGAGCCCAUGGAAAGGGAACUUACCUCUCUAUUGGGAAUCAGAGAAGUCUUCAUACAGUGGGUAAUGCAUGAUGUGAGUCCUGAAAAUCAGAGGAGUAGAUUAAUUGAUUAACCUUCUGUAAGAAAAGUCCUCCUAUAACAGAGGACUGCAAAUUAUUUGGCUUAAAUAUGAUGGAGAGGAGUUCAUUUUUCUCUCACAUAAAAGUCUAGCAGUGAAUAGUCCAAGAUCAAUGACAUACUUCUGCCAUCCUCACCACUUGGCUUCAGUUUCUUGAUCCUAGAUAGCUAUUCCAUUUGUCCCCAUUUACUAGCCAGAGAGAAAGGGAAAAAAAGACAGAAUGUAAUACAGACAGCUUCUUCAUAAAAGCAUGACCCAGAGGCUUUCAUGCAUUAUUUCUACUUGUAUUCUGUUAUCUAAAACUUAAUCACAUGUCCUUACCUAGCUGCAAGGGAGACUAAGAAAGGUAGGCAUGGGUGCCCAGCUACCAUUCAGUGACUUCCAUUAGUAAAAGUAAGAAGGGGAAGGUGGGUACCAGUAAGCAAUUAGCAGUCUCUUCCAUAAAGGGUAAGAGUGAAAGUGUUCUGUGUAUAGAUCACUCUGGAUACAUACAGGAAUGAGACACCAGAGAAAUUAAGUUCCAUAAAAUAACCAAAGAACUAAAUAACUAAGAGACUAAAGAACUUUAAUAAUUCAGCAUGGCUAUAGUGGAGGGUGAAUGUAGGGGAAUAGUGGAAGAUGGGGAAGAUGGGGCUGGAGAUUUCAGGAUGUGGCCAGAUUAUUGAGUACUUUGUGUGCUAACUAAGGAAUUUGGCCUUUGUCCCGAAGACAGUGAAGAGUCAUUGAAACAUUUUAAGCAGUGGAGUAACACAAUUAGAUUAGAGUUGAGAAAGAUCACUCUACCUGCACUUGGGUAGACAGAUUAAAGACAGGAGUGGCUGGAGACAGAAGGAACAAUUAGGAGACUAUUAUAAUCAUAGAGAGACAUGAUGAGACUCAACCAAGUCAGUGGUAGUGAGCAGAGGGGACAGAUUAGAGAGACAUUAAGGAAGUAUAAUUGAUAGAACUUGGUGACUAAAUGGAUGUGGGAUGUGAGAGAGGGGGAGGAUUUUAAGAUAAUAAUGUCCAGAUUUGUGGCUUGGACAUUGGCAUUGUUUUAGAUAAUAAAAAAUUUUAAGGGACGAAAGUGUUUAAUUCUAGAAAUGUUGAAUUUGAGAUACCUCUGGGAUAUCCAGAAGGCAACAUUGAGCAGUUAGUUAGAUAUAUUGGUAUAGAAACCAGUAGAGAAACUUGGUAGUGCAAGCCAUGUGAGUGGAUGACACGGUUGAGAAAGCGAAUGAGUGCAGACAAGUGAGAUCAUUAGAAGGUUGAGGACAUAAUCCUGGAGAACAUUAAAUUUCAGAGAGAGCCAGUGAAAGAGACGACAGUGUUCAGAGAAGCAGAAAGGUAAAGAGAGAGGAAUUUUUAGAAAUGGAUUGGUUAAAUGUGUUAAAUGUUGGAGCACAGUCAAAAUAAAAAUUGAAAAAGUACCUGUUGGAGUCAGCAAUCAGCAGGCCAGUGGUGAUCAUUGUAAAAACAGUUACAGAGGAGUGAUGUGGGCAGAGACAAGGUUGAGGAUCAACUGGAGGAUGAAGAAAUGGAGACUUAACUGUCUGGAAAGUGUAGAAGAAAAUGAAUGUGAUGGCAGUGGAGAGUAGCUUGGGUUCAGACAGGAGAGACUUAAGUUCAUUUAAAUGCUUUUGAGAAACAGUAUUGUAAGAAAGGAGAUGAAUGAUGGAGGAAGGUCCCUGAGAAACAGGAAGAGAUGAGAUGGGAUCCAGAGCAUAGGUAGAGGCAUUCUCCUUAGAAAGUGAGGAGAGAUAAAGUAGGUUUAUAAGUGUGGAUGUCAAUGAGUUUGUCAGUAUGGGGACAGAAAGUUGAAGUUGUUUACUUUAUUUAUUUAUUUAUUUAUUUAUUUAUUUAUUUAUUUAUUUUGAGACAGUCUUGCUCUGUUGUCCAGGAUGGAGUGCAGUGGUGCAAUCUGGGCUCACUGCAACCUCCACCUUCCAGAUUUGAGCAAUUCUCCUGCCUCAGCCUCCUGAGUAGCUGAGAUUACAGGCAUGCUGCAACAUGCCUGACUAAUUUUUGUACUAUUAAUAGAGCUAGGGUUUCACCAUGUUGGCCAGGCUUGUCUUGAACUCCUGGCCUCAAGGGAUCCGCCUGCCUCAGCCUCCCAAAGUGCUGAGAUUACAGACAUGAGCCACCGCGCCCAGCUGAAGAAGUUUACUUCUAAUGACCUCCCUUUUCUCUGAAGUAUGAGGUGACGCCAUCUGUGAGGGAGGGUGUCUAUGGUCUGGUAUAUUAUGAAUGGCUCAGCAAGGAUGUCUUCUAACUGAGCAAAGGGAAAUAAUAUAUGAUGCGUUUAUCUCCAUUAAUAACACUCACUUGGGUUCAAUCGGAAGAGAUUGUUGGAUGGACAGAUGCAUGGAUGGAUGCCUAUAAACAUAAUAAAUAUGUAUUCUGUUUUCCUCCACUCAAUGUUUUCAAAACGUUUUUUUAGAAGUUUAGUUCAGGGUUAAAAUUUUCUUGAAUCCCAUCUGCAUUAAGUAAGUAUAUUCUCAUUUGUUAUUCCUCUUCAUUAUUCUAGACCAACAUUUUUCAGCCUUGGUAUUAUUUUGACAUUUUGGGCCAAUAAUUCUUGUUGUGGGGACUGCCCUGGGCAUUGUUGGAUGUUUAGCAGGAUUCCUUGCCUUUCCCCACUAGAUGCCAACCCCCCUUCCACAGUUGUGACAAUAAAUAUUUUCACAGAUGUCAUGAAAUGUCCCCUGGAAAAUAGAAUUGGCCCCAUUUAAGAGGUUGUAUUCAAAACCAAAUGGAAGGGCCCUGGAGAGAGAGAGAGAGAAGGGGGAUUUAAGCUAGACAAAUACUCAUGUACAUUUAUCAGUUGAUCAUGACAACUAUACUCAUAGACAUGAUCUUCUUUUGGCAAAUUAGACAACUGAGGCUCAGAGAGGUUAAAUGACUUGCCUAACAUGACAGAGGCCAUAAGUGAUAGAGCUGGGGUUUGAACUCAUGUGUGUUAGAUCCCUACAAUUUAGGUUCUUUCUUAAGCAACAAUAAAAAAUAUUUUAGAGGGUGUCCUUGUUUUCAUUUUUAUUAUGUUUUAAAAAAUCAAACUAAACUUAAAAUUCAGCACAAAAAUUUAAAUAAUAUAGAAGUGUAUAGACUAAAACAGGAAUGUAUCUGUUGACAUUCCUCUGUAAUCCUAUUCACUUUCCUAGAGGUUAUGAUUGUGAUUGUUAACAAUUUAAUGUGUAUGCUUUUAGACCCUUUUCUUUGCAAUUAUAAAUGACAAAGGACAGUGCAUUCAUACACACACAAAACUAUUUUUGAAUAAUGACAUCAUACUAUAUAUACUAUUCCAUAAGCUACUUUAAAAUAUUUAAUCUUUCCACCUCAGUUCUUACAAAUCUACAUCACCACCUUUUAACAGUUGUGUAAUAUUCCUCAGUGAGUGAACCACAAUUUAUGUAACUUUCCCAUGUUAAUAGAUAUUUAUGUAGUUUUAUUUUUUUUAUGGUACAUGGAACUUGCAUAGAUAUCAGUGUGUGUAUGUGUCAGGAUUUCUGCUUAAUAGGGGUUUUAAAAGUAGGGAGAUCAGAGGUCUUGCCUAUUUAAAAUCAUGAUUGCUACUACCAGAUUGACCCCCAAUAUGGAUAAACCAAAUCAUCCUCCCAAUAACAGCUUAUAAAGGUGACUGUUUUUACCCACUUCUUUGUCAGUUUAGGACAAUAUCGAUUUUUCUUAAUUUAUCAGUCUAAUAGGCAAAAUGUGAUAUCUUGUUUGAAUUGUAGUUUUAUAAUUAUUAGUGAAGUUGAUUUUUAUGUUCACAAGCUAUUUCAUUUUCUUUUCCUUUGUAUGUCCUUUUCAGUGGCUGGUCGCUUCAAAAUCCUCCCCUCUCCAGGCCACUCCCACACUAAACUCUUCACCUAAGGCAACCACUAAUCAGUUCUGUUAGUAUAAUUUGUGUUUCCUAAAGUUUUGUAUAAACGGAAUAAUGCAGUAUAUACUUUUCUUUUGGUCUGGCUUCUUUGGUUCAGCAUAGUUAUUCUGAGAUUAAUUUAAGUUGUUAUAGUGAGUCAAUAGUUCAUUCCUUUUUAGUACUGAGUAGUAUUCCAUCAUAUAUACCAAAAUUUGGUUGUCUAUUCACUAGUUAAUGGACAUUUGGGUUGUUUCAGUUUGGGUCUGCUGCAAACAUUUGUGUACAGUCUGUACGACUAUAUGUUUUCUUUUUUCUUGAGUAAACAUGAAGGAGUAGAAAUGACUGAGUCACAUAGUAAUUAUACAUUUAAUUUUUAAAGAAAACGUAAAACAUUUUUCUUAAGUAACUGUAUCAUUGUACUUUCUGGAAGAGACUGUAAAACUCAUGUUAAUUCUGUAUAUGUUUGGUGGAAUCCUCCAGCUAAACUCUCUGGGUCUAGAGAUUUCUUCUUUGGAAGUUUUUAAACUAUGAAUUGAAAUUUUUUAAUGGUUAUAGGACUAUUCAGAUGAUCUAUUUCAUUGGGUGGUUUUUUUUUUUAAUUCACUAUGACAUUGUAUGAUUUUACAUUCCCAUCAGCAGUGAAAGUUCCAGUUCCUCCAUAUUCUUUUCAACAUGUGGUAUGGUCAGUCUAAAAAAUUUCAACCAUUCUAAUAGGUGUUCAGUGGCAUCGCAUCAUGUUUUUAGCAUGCAUUUCCCUAUUGACUUAAUGAUGUUGAACUUUUUUUAUGUUUGCCAUUUGUAUGUUUUCUUUGGUAAAGUGUCUAUUCAAAUAUUUUGCUUAUUCUUUAAAAACUGAUUUACUUGUUUUCUUAUUAUUGAGUUAUUGAGUUUUGGGAGUUCUUUAUAUAAUAUAUAUAUAAUACAAGUUCUUUAUCAGACAUAUGAUUUACAAAUAUUUUAACUCAGUCUGUGGUUUUUCUUUUCAUUCUUAACAGUGUCUUUUAGAAAAUCAUGAGUUUUCAAAUUUGAUGUUCAGUUUAUUGAUUAUUUUAUGAAUCAUUGUAUCUAAGAUAUCUUUGGCUAACCUAAGAUUACAAAGAUUUUUCUCCUCGAAAUUUUAUAGUUUCAGCUUUUAAAUUUGAUUAUAGCCCAUUCUGAGUUAGUUUUCUUCUGUGGUAUAAGAUACGAAUUGAAGUUUUUUUUUUUUUUUUUUUUUUGCCUAUGUAUAUCACAUUGUUCCAGUACCAUUGCUGUCCUUUCUCCACUGAAUUGCCUUUGUAAAAUAAAUAAAUAAAUUUAUCUGUAUAGA